ACAGCAACAGGACUCUCCAUGUGGCAAGGGCACCUGGAGGUGGGAGGGCAGGAGCGUCGUCUUGCCCUGGCAGAAGAAGCGGUAGGCUCUGUCUGCGUGGCAGCUGGUCCCCAGCCCUAGGAGAGAAGCUGUCUCCCUCAUUCCUCCUGAGUCCUGCUCCAGCCCCUUUGUCCCAGGGACCCUGGUAUCACCACCAACCCCUUGAUGAUGGAGUGACAUGCAGGGUCGUUUGCCAUGGCAGGUGUGAAAUACCCGGGACAGGACCCUGUGGAUUUAGACAUAUACCAAAGCUCCCACAUGGUCGACUAUCAGCCCUACAGGAAGCACAAAUACUCCAGGGUCACGCCGCAAGAGCAGGCAAAGCUCGAUGCUCAACUCCGGGACAAAGAGUUUUACAGGCCCAUCCCUAACCCCAACCCCAAGCUAACAGAUGGGUACCCUGCUUUCAAAAGACCCCACAUGACUGCCAAAGACCUGGGACUCCCCGGCUUCUUCCCAUCACAGGAACAUGAGGCCACGAGGGAGGACGAGCGCAAGUUCACCAGCACCUGCCAUUUCACAUAUCCAGCUUCCCACGAUCUGCACCUGGCCCAGGGUGACCCCAACCAGGUCCUCCAGAGUGCUGACUUUCCGUGCCUCGUGGAUCCCAAACACCAGCCUGCUGCAGAGAUGGCCAAAGGCUACCUGCUACUGCCAGGGUGUCCCUGUCUUCAUUGCCAUAUAGUCAAGGUCCCCAUCUUGAACCGGUGGGGACCCUUGAUGCCAUUUUACCAGUAGGAAGGAUGAAAAUACCUUCCAAAGGCUCUUCCAAGGGCAUGUGGAAAUCCUAUGACCUUGGAGUGCAGAGAGGAGAACUGAAAAUAAAACUGGAAAGAUGUUCCAACUGCA